AUCAAAGCAGCGGCCGGCUGUUGGGGUCCACCACGCCUUCCACCUGCCCCACUGCUUCUUCGCUUCUCUCUUGGAAAGUCCAGUCUCUCCUCGGCUUGCAAUGGACCCCAACUGCUCCUGCGCCGCUGGUGUCUCCUGCACCUGCGCUGGUUCCUGCAAGUGCAAAGAGUGCAAAUGCACCUCCUGCAAGAAGAGUGAGUGUGAGGCCAUCUCCAUGGUCUGGGGCUGUGGCUAAGGCUGCUGCUCCUGCUGCCCCGUGGGCUGUAGCAAGUGUGCCCAGGGCUGUGUUUGCAAAGGGGCGUCAGAGAAGUGCAGCUGCUGCGACUGAUGCCAGGACAACCUUUCUCCCAGAUGUAAACAGAGAGACAUGUACAAACCUGGAUUUUUUUUUUAUACCACCUUGACCCAUUUGCUACAUUCCUUUUCCUGUGAAAUAUGUGAGUGAUAAUUAAACACUUUAGACCUGA